AAAGUCUCGCUCUGUCCUCAGAGGCAGGAGUACAAUGGUGUGAUCAUAGCUCACUAUCACCUUGAAAUCCAGGACCGAAACGAUCCUCCCACCUCAGCCUCCUGAGUAGCUGGGAUUACAGGAGCAGUUUCAGUCUCAACUUCAAAAGAACAAACGCGCACUCAAAACAAAGGAAGACCGUCCUCGACUGCAGAGGAAGCAGGAAGCUGUCGGCCCAGCUCUGAGCCCAGCUGCUGGAGCCCCGAGCAGCGGCAUGGAGUCCGUGGCCCUGUACAGCUUUCAGGCUACAGAGAGCGACGAGCUGGCCUUCAACAAGGGAGACACACUCAAGAUCCUGAACAUGGAGGAUGACCAGAACUGGUACAAGGCCGAGCUCCGGGGUGUCGAGGGAUUUAUUCCCAAGAACUACAUCCGCGUCAAGCCCCAUCCGUGGUACUCGGGCAGGAUUUCCCGGCAGCUGGCCGAAGAGAUUCUGAUGAAGCGGAACCAUCUGGGAGCCUUCCUGAUCCGGGAGAGUGAGAGCUCCCCAGGGGAGUUCUCUGUGUCUGUGAACUAUGGAGACCAGGUGCAGCACUUCAAGGUGCUGCGUGAGGCCUCGGGGAAGUACUUCCUGUGGGAGGAGAAGUUCAACUCCCUCAACGAGCUGGUCGACUUCUACCGCACCACCACCAUCGCCAAGAAGCGGCAGAUCUUCCUGCGCGACGAGGAGCCCUUGCUCAAGUCACCUGGGGCCUGCUUUGCCCAGGCCCAGUUUGACUUCUCAGCCCAGGACCCCUCGCAGCUCAGCUUCCGCCGUGGCGACAUCAUUGAGGUCCUGGAGCGCCCAGACCCCCACUGGUGGCGGGGCCGGUCCUGCGGGCGCGUUGGCUUCUUCCCACGGAGUUACGUGCAGCCCGUGCACCUGUGAGCAGCCCGGCGGCCGAUCUGGCCAACGGGCCUUUUUACAGGAACUGAGGUCCAGAGAGGACAUGGACACCCCCAGCUCUGUCAGAGUCACACGGGGCUCAGUGGACGGCCUUGGACUGAACGUGGGCUCCUAACUGCCUCCGGCCGCUCUGCACAAACUGGGAUGGCCCAGGUCCCCCAGCAAGGGUACCCAGCAAGGGUAGCUCCGGGGCUUCCUGGCUGGUUGCUUUCCAUUGGCUGCCAGCUGUGUGACACCACAGGGCGGAGUCUGUGGAGGCCCCGCCCACCUCCUCUUGUCAAUGGCCCCAUCUGCCAGGAAGGUUGAGGACUCCCAGGUUUCACCCACUGGAGGCUCAACCUAAGGAACCCUGGCCAUGGUGGGUGGGUUCACCUUGGGCUGACCACCCACUGGGCCUGCCUGCCCCUCCCUCAAAAGGCCCCUGGAGUUGUUCAGGCUGUUGGGAGGUGGCUCAGCCUCGAAGGACAGACUGCACACCUGUUGACCUAAACUCACUGGACAGACUCCAGGUGGACACCAACUCCUCAACAGCCCCAUGACUUCAGCUCCACCUGGGGCACCCAGCACCCCACCACAGGGCUAGAGGCCCUAAGACCCUGAAAAAGGGGCGGGCAGUAGGGAAGGUGGAGGCACACUCCUCUUCUGUUGGACAGGUGAGCUCUGAGGGCAAGCCCUGGGCCCAGCCACGCAGAGACCCUGGCUGCCCUGGCUCUUGUUUGUUUAGGCCCAGGUUCUGCCCAGACCGGGGCCCAGCAGAGCUCUCAGGAGGCUGAGAAACCUCCAGGGCAGACAGAAAGUUGGGGCCAGAGCUAGGUUUUAGAGAUCCUACAGGAUCCCACAUGGGACGGCUACCUAGGUGGGGCACGGCCCCUACCCGAGAACAGGAGGGUCCUCCAGAGAAUGUGCCAUGAUCAGGGAUAUGAGCAGGGCCUGCCCAGAGCCUGGGCACCUUUGGGAGAGGGAAAAGUGAGGUGGGACUUGGAAAGGCUUUGAACGCCAGGCUGAUGGUUGAGGGAUGGUGGGCAGGGAGGGAGGGCGAAGAGGCUCCCUCUGGCAUUUGGGAGCCGGUGGGUGGAGGGAGGAGCCCUUGGAGGUGGCUGCAGUCCCUUAAUGGGGGGCCUUGCUCUGGGCAUGUGGGGCUCUUCCUCCAUCCAGAGCUGGCCCAAGACCCUUAGAACCCUGAGUGCUGGCAAAUCUCACUGCUCCUGACCCAGCCUGUGUAUUCAAAACGAAAACAGUAAAACCAACAUCAGGAUGUCCGUCAGAAAUCUAAUUUUCCUUCCAA